GUGACAUGCUAAGUUACCUAACCAUGGUGUGGAAGGAGAGGGAAAUGGAGUGAAGUUGGGGACCCACCAGGGAACAGGUGGCUUGAGGGCGGGGGGAGCAUGAAGGUAAGGGCUUGUUUGGGGGCUCAAGGCAGUCUGAGCCUUGUUCGCAGGCAGCCAGUGUCCACCAGGUGUGUGCAGAUGGGACAGCUUGGCCUACAGCCCGGCGGGCAUCAGCUCCCUUGACCCAGUGGAUAUCGGUGGCCCCGUUAUUCGUCCAGGUGCCCAGGGAGGAGGACCCGCCUGCAGCAUGAACCUGUGGCUCCUGGCCUGCCUGGUGGCCGGCUUCCUGGGAGCCUGGGCCCCCGCUGUCCACACCCAAGGUGUCUUUGAGGACUGCUGCCUGGCCUACCACUACCCCAUUGGGUGGGCUGUGCUCCGGCGCGCCUGGACUUACCGGAUCCAGGAGGUGAGCGGGAGCUGCAAUCUGCCUGCUGCGAUAUUCUACCUCCCCAAGAGACACAGGAAGGUGUGUGGGAACCCCAAAAGCAGGGAGGUGCAGAGAGCCAUGAAGCUCCUGGAUGCUCGAAAUAAGGUUUUUGCAAAGCUCCACCACAACACGCAGACCUUCCAAGCAGGCCCUCAUGCUGUAAAGAAGUUGAGUUCUGGAAACUCCAAGUUAUCAUCGUCCAAGUUUAGCAAUCCCAUCAGCAGCAGUAAGAGGAAUGUCUCCCUCCUGAUAUCAGCUAAUUCAGGACUGUGAGCCGGCUCAUUUCUGGGCUCCAUCGGCACAGGAGGGGCCGGAUCUUUCUCCGAUAAAACCGUCGCCCUACAGACCCAGCUGUCCCCACGCCUCUGUCUUUUGGGUCAAGUCUUAAUCCCUGCACCUGAGUUGGUCCUCCCUCUGCACCCCCACCACCUCCUGCCCGUCUGGCAACUGGAAAGAGGGAGUUGGCCUGAUUUUAAGCCUUUUGCCGCUCCGGGGACCAGCAGCAAUCCUGGGCAGCCAGUGGCUCUUGUAGAGAAGACUUAGGAUACCUCUCUCACUUUCUGUUUCUUGCCGUCCACCCCGGGCCAUGCCAGUGUGUCCCUCUGGGUCCCUCCAAAACUCUGGUCAGUUCAAGGAUGCCCCUCCCAGGCUAUGCUUUUCUAUAACUUUUAAAUAAACCUUGGGGGGUGAUGGAGUCA